GCAUUACACGCCGGUCAGGAUUCGCGACCCGACAUGGAGCGUCCCCGCAGUCCCCAAUGCUCGGCCCCGGCCUCUGCCUCAGCUUCGGUUACCCUGGCGCAGCUCCUGCAGCUGGUCCAGCAGGGCCAGGAACUCCCGGGCCUGGAGAAACGCCACAUCGCGGCGAUCCACGGCGAACCCACAGCGUCCCGGCUGCCGCGGAGGCCCAAGCCCUGGGAGGCCGCGGCUUUGGCUGAGUCCCUUCCCCCUCCGACCCUCAGGAUAGGAACGGCCCCGGCGGAGCCUGGCUUGGUUGAGGCAGCGACUGCGCCUUCUUCAUGGCAUACAGUGGGCCCCUGAGGUUCCAGGUCCUUUGCGGCGGCGAUCUGGAGGGCGUGGCUACAGGACCCGGGAUGCCAUUCAGUUACUCAUCUUUUAUGCUUUCGUCCUGACCUGUCUCAACUAGACUUGCUCCUGCAACCACCAUGGGGGUUUUGCAUUUACAUUUGUGGACCAUGUUACAGUUAAGAAAAAUCCUGUUUCAGUCCUUAUAUGUAAUAAAAUGUUUUAUGAUGUAA